GCACUCUGGGGCCCACGCACUUCCCUGAAGAGUCUAGAAGCUGCUCCUCAUUUCCAGACUUUCCGGGCGCCCACCAGGCUCCCGGGCUCUCACCGGAGACCACAGGGAGGAGCUUCAAGGUACCCCAAGUCCCUGCGGCCUCCAGCAGUGAAGAGUUCCACAAGGGAGUCUUCCUACGUCACUGAAUAAUGAAUGAAGAUGAGAGGGGAAAAGAGAAGAGACAAAGUCAAUCCAAAAAGCUCUCAAAGGAAAUUAAACUGGAUUCCAUCAUUUCCUACCUAUGAUUACUUCAACCAAGUGACGCUACAGUUAUUAGAUGGCUUUAUGAUUACACUGAGCACAGAUGGAGUGAUCAUUUGUGUGGCUGAAAACAUCUCUUCUCUUCUUGGACAUUUACCAGCUGAGAUUGUGGGCAAAAAAUUAUUAAGCCUUCUGCCUGAUGAAGAGAAAGAUGAAGUCUACCAAAAGAUUAUUCUCAAAUUUCCUUUACUAAACUCAGAAACACAUAUUGAAUUUUGCUGUCAUUUAAAAAGAGGAAAUGUCGAACAUGGUGAUAGUUCUGCUUACGAAAACGUGAAAUUUAUUGUGAAUGUAAGAGAUAUUUGUAAUGAGUUUCCUGUGGUCUUUAGUGGCUUGUUUUCCAGCCACCUCUGUGCUGACUUUGCUGCAUGUGUUCCUCAGGAGGAUCGGCUUUAUCUUGUGGGAAAUGUUUGCAUUCUCAGGACUCAGCUCCUGCAGCAACUUUACACUUCAAAGGCAGUCAGUGAUGAAGCUGUACUUACACAAGAUUCAGAUGAGGAACCUUUUGUGGGAGAGCUCAGUAGCUCUCAAGGUCAAAGAGGACACACUAGCAUGAAAGCCGUGUACGUUGAACCCGCUGCUGCUGCUGCUGCUGCUGCUAUCUCAGACGACCAAAUUGAUAUUGCAGAGGUUGAGCAGUAUGGACCACAAGAAAACGUUCACAUGUUUGUAGAUUCUGAUUCAACUUAUUGCUCCAGUACAGUUUUCCUGGAUACUAUGCCUGAAUCUCCAGCCUUAUCCUUGCAAGACUUUCGAGGUGAGCCUGAGGUGAAUCCAUUGUACAGGGCAGACCCAGUGGACCUGGAGUUCUCGGUGGAUCAGGUGGACUCAGUGGACCAGGAGGGCCCAAUGGACCAGCAGGACCCAGAGAACCCAGUUGCCCCGUUGGACCAGGCAGGCCUGAUGGAUCCAGUGGAUCCAGAGGACUCAGUGGACCUGGGGGCUGCUGGCGCAAGUGCUCAGCCAUUACAGCCAUCAUCACCAGUUGCAUAUGACAUCAUUAGCCAGGAACUGGAACUGAUGAAGAAGUUGAAGGAGCAGCUAGAAGAGAGGACUUGGUUGCUGCAUGAUGCCAUCCAAAACCAGCAGAAUGCAUUGGAAUUGAUGAUGGAUCACCUUCAGAAGCAGCCAAACACAUUACGCCACGUUGUCAUUCCUGAUCUCCAAUCUUCGGAGGCAGUGCCCAAGAAACAACAGAAACAACACGCUGGGCAAGUGAAGCGGCCUCUCCCACAUCCCAAGGACGUCAAGUGUUUCUGUGGUUUAUCUUUAUCCAACUCUCUCAAAAACACUGGGGAGCUUCAGGAGCCUUGUGUUGCCUUCAACCAGCAGCAACUGGUGCAGCAAGAACAACACCUGAAGGAGCAGCAGCGGCAGCUGCGGGAGCAGCUGCAACAGCUGAGAGAGCAAAGGAAGGUGCAGAAGCAGAAGAAGAUGCAGGAGAAGAAGAAGCUGCAGGAGCAGAAAAUGCAGGAGAAGAAGAAGCUGCAGGAGCAGAGGCGGCAAAAGAAGAAGAAGCUACAGGAGCGGAAGAAGUGGCAGGGGCAGAUGCUACAGAAAGAGCCAGAGGAGGAGCAGCAGAAGCAGCAGCUGCAAGAGCAGCCACUGAAGCAUAAUGUCAUCGUGGGGAAUGAGAGGGUGCAGAUAUGCCUGCAAAACCCACGUGACGUAUCUGUGCCCCUCUGCAAUCACCCUGUUAGAUUUUUACAGGCCCAACCCAUUGUUCCUGUCCAGAGAGCAGCUGAACAACAGCCCUCUGGCUUCUAUCAAGAUGAAAACUGUGGGCAACAGGAAGAUGAGAGUCAAAGUUUUUAUCCUGAGGCGUAUCAAGGGCCCCCCGUGAACCAGCUGCCAUUGAUAGAUACCUCAAACUCUGAGGCAAUUUCUUCUUCCAGCAUUCCUCAGUUUCCCAUAACUUCAGACUCAACCAUAAGCACCCUGGAGACCCCACAGGAUUACAUCCGGCUUUGGCAAGAGUUGUCUGAUUCACUCGGUCCUGUUGUCCAAGUGAACACUUGGUCUUGCGAUGAGCAGGGCACCCUGCACGGCCAACCCACCUACCAUCAGGUGCAAGUUUCUGAGGUAGGAGUCGAGGGACCUCCUGAUCCACAGGCUUUCCAAGGCCCUGCUGCAUACCAGCCAGACCAGAUGAGAUCUGCGGAGCAGACCAGAUUGAUGCCUGCAGAGCAACGUGACUCAAAUAAGCCGUGCUAACAGUACUUUCAUGACCAGUGAUGAGGGGAAAUGGGGGGAGGGGGCAGGCCAAUGAGGUCUGCAUGGCCAGGGGACCUUCAAGGUGCGUAAAGUCCCUUGGGGUAGGGUUUAGUGGGUAGAGACUUAUUUGUUUCCUGAUAGGUUAUGUUUGUAAUUGUUUGUUAAGCACAGCCUGUUUCUUGGAAGUUAUGCUGUAGAGGCAGCCUGUGAUCCGUAGUAUGCUAGGGUGUGACAGCAGCCAGCCACAGCUGGAUCUGAUGUCUUGUCUGCCCCGCCCAGCUUUGCAUAUCCAUGUUCUACCACAGGAAGGUGGCCUGCCAAGAGUCUGCUCAAAGUUUUCAACAUAAAGAAUAAAGAAAAAAAAAUGCCAAAGUGCUUUUCAAUCUAGUAAAUCUAGAGGGUUGUUUUGUCUUAGCCACAAGAAUUCCGAGGUCUUGACCCUGAUGAUCAACCUGCCUCCCCUCCAUAGUCUUGUUGGAGAAGCCCAGAGAGAAUGGGACUCCAACUAAGGGAACCUGAAAUCAACUCAAUGGAGGCACUUCAGAGCUAAAAUAAUUAUGGCUUCCUUGCUUAAUAAACAUUUUCGUUCACUGCAA